AGGGCGGAGGCCGCGCCGGGAGCGCGGUGGGGCUAGGCGUGGGGCGCUCCCGGCAUGUCCCUGUACCGCAGCGUCGUGUGGUUCGCCAAGGGGCUGCGCGAGUACACCAAGAGUGGCUAUGAAUCUGCAUGUAAAGACUUUGUCCCUCAUGACUUGGAGGUCCAGAUUCCUGGAAGAGUCUUUUUGGUCACUGGAGGAAACAGCGGCAUUGGCAAAGCAACUGCCCUUGAAAUCGCCAAGCGAGGUGGCACAGUUCACCUGGUUUGUCGAGAUCAAGCCCCAGCAGAAGAUGCCAGGGGUGAGAUCAUCCGGGAGAGCGGUAACCAGAACAUUUUUCUGCACAUUGUGGACUUGUCUGAUCCCAAGCAAAUCUGGAAAUUUGUUGAAAAUUUCAAGCAGGAACAUAAACUCCAUGUUCUGAUCAAUAAUGCAGGUUGCAUGGUCAAUAAAAGAGAGCUCACAGAAGAUGGACUUGAAAAAAACUUUGCUGCCAAUACUCUGGGUGUGUACAUUCUCACGACCGGCCUGAUCCCUGUGCUGGAGAAAGAACACGACCCCCGAGUGCAGAAGGGACUUGGCAGCUGCAGUUCAGUUCAAGGCCUUGGGAUGAGAAGCGUGUCCUGGAGUAUCCAGAUAACCGUCUCCUCAGGAGGAAUGUUGGUUCAGAAACUGAACACCAAUGAUCUCCAGUCCGAAAGAACACCAUUUGAUGGAACUAUGGUCUAUGCACAAAACAAGGUCAGUGAGAGGCAGCAAGUGGUUCUGACGGAGCGGUGGGCCCAAGGGCACCCGGCCAUCCAUUUUUCUUCCAUGCAUCCUGGCUGGGCCGACACCCCAGGAUACCACAAAUCUCUUGGUGGCAAAGGAGAGCUUUUACUGCUUGCCGUGGACUAUAUUCUAAACCAGCAGAAACUAGAGCAACCUGAGUGAUGGUUGCGGCGCUGAGUGCAAGGCUCAGAUUAAAUUCUCGCCUUAACCUGAAGCGGUCUGCAGGCUGCAGGAACUUACUCUUCAUCUGUGAUGGCCUCGUGGCAGCUGUCACAGACCCUCACUUCAAACUCGAAGCCCAUCAGGGGGAUGGAGGAGCGCUUGGAGCUGCACUUGCCACAGACGGCCUUCCCACACUUGCGGCAGUGGUGCUGGAGGAGGGAGAUAAAAUAGAUACUCAUCACGGCUCCCUCAGCUCCUGAGGCCCCCGCAUCUCACCCCUCCUGGCAGAGAGGUGUAAUCAACUGCAUCCAGGUGAGGAUGCUGAACAAGAGAGCCCCAGAACUAAAGGGAACACAUUGGAUGUGUUCUUCUCUGGGGCUCUGUUUAUUCAACAAGGACUGUUGGGUAACACACCUGACAGGGAUACCACCCCACUCUCCUGCUUUCCCUACUCUUGGUCCUUUCCAAUGAUCAUACUAGGAACUACAGAGGAACCACCCAGGGGCCAGGUGAUCUUAAAGCGGGGUGUCUGAGAAACUGCCGUCUCAGGAGAUUAUGCUGCUGGAUGAAGGAGAACAUGCAGGAAACCUGAUUGAAUCUGCUGACUUUGGCCAUGGUAAGCCUAGGUGACCUAACAUUUGAUUUCCUUGGGGAAGACCAAACAGAACCAUGGAAUCAGAUUGAAAAUGCUGUAUUAUAAGUAGAUCUAAAUAACUAAAAUUAAUCAGAAGGAGGGAAAGUAAAAUAAGGAGAGAGAAACACCACUUAUAUAAUUUCAUGGUCUGGUUUCCAUACGAACUAAGCAUGACACCUCUAAUUGUAAGGUGCACUGCAAUAGAGGCCAACAGAAUUCUAAAAUCACAUCCCUAACUGCUUACUGGGAACCAACCACUACAGAAACUGAAUCCAGUAGGAAUGGGCUAUGGUAGACAGAGUAAAUUACUGUGCAAUCACGAGGUGACUCCAGGAUAAUAAUUUACCCUCACCACAACUCCCACCCAGGGGUGUUAUUUCUUCUAAGAUCACAUGGUUGAGCUAUUUCCAUAUAAUUACAUUUUGAUGAAGCAUCCAUAUCACUCACCUGUCUUAGACCAAUUUUCUUACUGUCCCACAUUUGCUUGAAGUUCCAGAAGAAAGGCUGAUCACACUUUUGGCAGGAAUCACUGUCCAACCAUUCAGGGGUCUUGUCAAAUAAAGCACAGAACAGGUCACUGUGGCCAGCAGUCAGGACAAUGGAAACCACUGACCCUGAUGAAACUUAUGGAGCUAUCAGGAUGUGUUUAAAAGAAACAGAGGUGUGAUUUCUCAGUCAAUCAUUCAAAAAAUAUUUACUGAAUGCCUAUUCUGUGGCAGGCCCUGGGGAUGGGAUGUAGUGGUGAAUAAGAAUCUCCACCAUCAUGAAAAUAUGAUUAAUAAUUAUUUACAUAAGCAUAAGUGUGUGAAGGCCCAAGAGGGAGAAGCACAGAGUGCUUUGGCAGAGAGAUCACAGGAGCCUCUGACCCAGGCUGAGGUUCUCAGACAAAUAAGACAACUGAGACCUGGGGAUGGCUGGAGCACAGAUGGGGAAAUGAGAGAUGAGGCUGGAGGGGGCAGUAUUAAUGUUUGUUUGUGAAACAAUUUCUCAAAUACCAGCUUAUUACCAUUAAAAUUAUGUAGUAAAAACAAAUAAAUAUUUAAAGACAUGGAA